ACUUGGUCUCCUGCUUUCGCGACAUGGCCUUCAAUUUUGGGGCUCCCUCGGGCACCUCCGGUACCGCUGCAGCCACCGCGGCCCCCGCGGGUGAGUGAUCCCCCUAGACCUUCACCCGGGAAGAAGGGGAAGGGUCUGGUCCGCCCCCUCUGUCCGAGACUCUCCGACCUGGGGAUCCUGGAAUCUCCCGCCGACGCGGAGACUUUAGAGGCAUUGGAAAAGGGCGGGCGGCGGCAGAGUGGGCCGAGGCGGCACCCGAGGAGGCCACGGGGGUACUCGGGGUCCCACUAGAAGCUCGCUUGCCGCGCGUGAGUUUCCACAGGGCCCUGGCUUGAGCGGUUCGCUUCCCGCUGCCGGGGAGUCCUACUCAGAGAAAUUGGAGGUUGCUUCCCUCUCCCCUUGCCCGAGAACCUCCCUCCCCUCUGCACCUCAGCCUCCUGGAUGGGCGGGAACGCUUGCGUGGUUCCCGCUGCCGGACUCGGCGAGGAUAGGGCUGGGGAUCCACCGGCACUGCCCAUUGACUCCCUUAGUUCCACCCCCGGCCCCCUGUGGUCCUCGCUGUGGGGUUUAUCCGUCAUGCUUCUUCCAUCUGCCCCACCCCACCCCCACUCUGCUUUCUUAAACUGUUUGGAGCAAAACCAGGUUUGUUCACUUCUGUGAAACCUCCUGCUGAUUCUUCUAAUCCUUAUCUUGCUUUCUUUUCUUUUUCCCUCUCCCCCUUUUUAAAAUUUUGUUUCUUUGCCUACACGCCUAUCAGGAUUUGGUGGGCUUGAGACUGCCAACUCCACCGCCAGUGGGUUUAAUUUUGGGGGUUUCGGAUUAACUGCUAAUCCUGCAGUGAACUUUAAUAUUGGGAAUUUCGGUGUUUCUACUACCUCGGCGACUCCGUUCAAUUUUGGUAACAGUCUGGCAAGUGCAGGUAGAUACUGCGGGUUGUAUGUGUAACCAGUGUUGGGAGCUGGAGUCCAAGAAUAUUGUGGUUCCUGGAGUUUGGGAAAGAACAGUUACUUGUCUAAUAGGGAAAGGAAAUUUAUUUCCUUAUCUCGAAUCAAAAACAUCUGUAUCAAGUUUUUACUGCCUUAAAAGAUGUGGUUUAGGAAAGUUUUGCAAGUUACAGUGUUCCUUUAUUAAAUGUGCACUUAUCUUCCAAAUGAUAAGCAUUUGGAUUAUAAUUUUGAAUAGAUCUUUAAAAUUAUUAGGUAGGACUUCCAAAGUAUAAACUCACCACCAGUCAAGCCCAUCCUGGGAUUCUUGGACUCCUGCAGUCAUUUUUCAUUUUUUCUGCAUCUUUCAUUGAGAUUUCAUUUUAUUGUCCUUGUGUUUCCAAAGAGAAACAAGUCUUAUACGAACAGCAGUAACCUGUUUUGUUUUUUAACUUGUGUUAUAAUGAUAAUAAUGUAUUUCUUUGGUCAACUCAGCAGAUUAGGAUACUAUAAGAUGUGUAAUUUCUAUAAGAUUUGUAAUUAUAGAAAGAAUCCCCAGUUCUUUGCUGGAAUUUUGGGAAAUGCUCAAAGAGAGCAGUUUAGUUUUAUGUGAUAUAGCAUCGAAUUCUAAAAGGUAAGCUAGACGUCUUUGCAUUCAAAAAGAUAAUUAUGAAGAUUUUCAUAUGCACGUGGGUUGUUUGCAGCUCAUUAGAAAUUUUGCAAAACAAUAAUGAUAUAUACAUUUAAAAUAGGUUUAUGGGUACUUUACAUAGUGACACUGUAGAAAAAAACUUGUUCUUCAGCUGCUCGUAUAUGAAUUUAUCGUCCAUAGUCUCUUACGUUAUGCCUCUUGUGCCCAUGCCAAUUAUAUGCAUUUGAUAAACAUUAUUUACUCCCUAAAAGUUAAUUGGGAAGUUUGUUAUUUUGUUCAUUCACUGGUUACUGCAAUGUGAUUAUCACCCUAGCAUCUGAGUUGAAAACAGUUCGAAGAAUAUUUGAAAACUUCAAAGACAAGAUGAUGCAUUUUAAUUAAGAUGUAUUCGAAGUAAUCACAUAUCACUGUCCUUUGAUGUGUUUACUUUUCCUUGUUUGCUUAAAAUUGGCACUGGGUAAAACAGAAAUCUUACUUUGAAAUUUGUGUUUCUGAAUAAAGCCACCCAGCUCAUAAUUCAACAACAAUAAAUAAACUUGUUGGUAUUUGCUUGAUUUCAUGUUCAUUUGGAGUUAUCACUGUUAAGUUUUGAGUUAUGAUAAUGUAAUAUGUUUUAACUACUUUUAUAUGUGUUAACCUUCAGCAAAGGGCUGAUAGACUUUCUUGUUUACUUUUUAUUUUGUAUACUUGCAGAUCUGCUAUUACUAAAACAUUUUUGAUGUUGUGGAGCAUGAUGAGAAACUGACUAGUGUUUCUAUUGCGUAGCCAAUUCAGAUUAUAUCAUAGUUAUUCUAUGGAAGUGAAGAAUAAUGAAAAGAAAUUACAACAGUGCUUAGUACUGUGGGUGACUUUUAUGAAAAUGUUUAUAGUUUGCAGUACUGCAGUAGAACCUACAAGUAAAUAGAAUAUUUAGUUGUGCCUGCAUGCAACAUGCAGCUUACUCUUGAGUAGUUUUCCAAAUCAGAAUGAGGUGAUUAAUAUAAAAUGGUUGCAUGUUUUUCUUCUUGUAUUUUCUAUAUUGCAAUAUUGAUGAAUCUGUGUUGUAUACCAGAAAUAAAUGAGAUUAAAGGAAGAUUCCAAAAAAUCUGCAAUAUAAUUCGACACUAAUGGUUCAAACAUUUGUCUUGAAAGGCUUUUUGAUACCACAUUGGUAAUCAGCUGAAGACUGACAAUAAGUUACAAAAAUAACAAAACAAUUUUAGAUUGGCUAGCAUUCCAUUUAUCUGUCAAAUCUCUUCCUUCAAGAAACACAUUCUUGUUGUUUGGAGGUGGGUUUGGAGGAUUUGGGACAACAUCUACAACUGCAGGUUCUGCAUUCAGCUUUUCUGCCCCAACUAACACAGGCACUACUGGACUCUUUGGUGGUACUCAGAACAAAGGUUUUGGAUUUGGUACUGGUUUUGGCACAACAACGGGAACUAGUACUGGUUUAGGUACUGGUUUGGGAACUGGACUGGGAUUUGGAGGAUUUAAUACACAGCAGCAGCAGCAAACUACAUUAGGUGGUCUCUUCAGUCAGCCUACACAAGCUCCUACCCAGUCCAACCAGCUGAUAAAUACUGCGAGUGCUCUUUCUGCUCCAACGCUGUUGGGAGAUGAGAGAGAUGCUAUUUUGGCAAAAUGGAAUCAACUGCAGGCCUUUUGGGGAACAGGAAAAGGGUAUUUCAACAAUAAUAUUCCGCCAGUGGAAUUCACACAAGAAAAUCCCUUUUGCCGAUUUAAGGCAGUAGGUUAUAGUUGCAUGCCCAGUAAUAAAGAUGAAGAUGGGCUAGUGGUUUUAGUUUUCAACAAAAAAGAAACAGAGAUUCGAAGCCAACAACAACAGUUGGUAGAAUCAUUGCAUAAAGUUUUGGGAGGAAACCAGACCCUUACUGUAAAUGUAGAGGGCACUAAAACAUUGCCAGAUGAUCAGACAGAAGUUGUUAUUUAUGUUGUUGAGCGUUCGCCAAAUGGUACUUCAAGAAGAGUUCCAGCUACAACGCUAUAUGCCCAUUUUGAACAAGCCAAUAUAAAAACACAAUUGCAGCAACUUGGUGUAACCCUUUCUAUGACUAGAACAGAACUUUCUCCUGCACAGAUCAAACAGCUUUUACAGAAUCCUCCUGCUGGUGUUGAUCCUAUUAUCUGGGAACAGGCCAAGGUAGAUAACCCUGAUUCUGAAAAGUUAAUUCCUGUACCAAUGGUGGGUUUUAAGGAACUUCUCCGAAGACUGAAGGUUCAAGAUCAGAUGACUAAGCAGCAUCAAACCAGAUUAGAUAUCAUAUCUGAAGAUAUUAGUGAGCUACAAAAGAAUCAAACUACAUCUGUAGCCAAAAUUGCACAAUACAAGAGGAAACUCAUGGAUCUUUCCCAUAGAACUUUACAGGUCCUAAUCAAACAGGAAAUUCAAAGGAAGAGUGGUUAUGCCAUUCAGGCUGAUGAAGAGCAGUUGCGAGUUCAGCUGGAUACGAUUCAGGGUGAACUAAAUGCACCUACUCAGUUCAAGGGCCGACUAAAUGAAUUGAUGUCUCAAAUCAGGAUGCAGAAUCAUUUUGGAGCAGUCAGAUCUGAAGAAAGGUAUUACAUAGAUGCAGAUCUGUUACGAGAAAUCAAGCAGCAUUUGAAACAACAACAGGAAGGCCUUAGCCAUUUGAUUAGCAUCAUUAAAGACGAUCUAGAAGAUAUAAAGCUGGUCGAACAUGGAUUGAAUGAAACCAUCCACAUCAGAGGUGGUGUCUUUAGUUGACAGUUCACAAACUUGUGUAAAGGUUUGUGAAAUGCAUCUUCUUACUGCAUCAGACCUUCCUUAAGAAUGAAACCGACCACAUGGAGGGAAAAAGAAAACAAUUCUUUCUUGGAUUGGUUUUUUGAGAAGUUUACUGACAAAUUACUGUUCAUCAAAUCUGAAAUAGUCACCUCACAGCUCUUCAAAGAAAACCUUUGAAAGAUUUAUAUCUAAAAGCUGUAUUUACUUUAAAAGAAGUGCAUAAUUACCAAAAUUGUAUGUACUAUUGUACAUUUUUACAACAGCAUUUUCUUAAACAUAAUCUGUGUUUAAUGAUUAUUGUCCAUUGAGCCUGUACUCUGCUUUCCAUACCAAGUAAAUAUGAAAUAAUCUACUUUGCACAUAACAGAACAAACUAUAAUUACUUGGCUGUUGGAGAUUUGUACUUGAGUAUAAAUGUACACCAGUUUUUGUAUUUGUGAACUCAUCUGUGGGAGGAGUAAAGAAAAUCCAAAAGCAUUUAAUGUUUUGUUUUUGUUCUAUAAAGAUAUGAAAAUGUAUUUUUAUAUUAUUUUACUUAUUUGGAAUUUACAGAGCACACCUAAGCAAUUAGGAUAUAACAAAACUACUUAACCAUUUUUGCAACCAUUUUGUUUUUUAAGCCUUUUUAUUUCUAAAAAGAUGAAAACUUAUAAAUAAAUUCUUAAUUUGUAAUUACUUUUA